CCUCCCGGAAGCGCAGAGCUCCGCUGGUGCCACGUCUAUCCCCUUACAUCCUCCUAGGACCCGGUCGGUAGUCGUCGCCCCAGCCCGCCGGGGGCGCAGCGCCCGAGCCGCGGCCCUCGAGACGGGACCGAGAGCAUCAUGGGCAGCACUGUCCCGCGCUCCGCCUCCGUGCUGCUUCUGCUGCUGCUCCUGCGCCGGGCCGAGCAGCCCUGCGGGGCCGAGCUCACCUUCGAGCUGCCGGACAACGCCAAGCAGUGCUUCCACGAGGAGGUGGAGCAGGGCGUGAAGUUCUCCCUGGAUUACCAGGUCAUCACUGGAGGCCACUACGAUGUUGACUGCUAUGUAGAGGACCCCCAGGGGAACACCAUCUACAGAGAAACGAAGAAGCAGUACGACAGCUUCACGUACCGGGCUGAAGUCAAGGGCGUUUAUCAGUUUUGCUUCAGUAAUGAGUUUUCCACCUUCUCUCACAAGACCGUCUACUUUGACUUUCAAGUGGGCGAUGAGCCUCCCAUUCUCCCAGACAUGGGGAACAGGGUCACAGCUCUCACCCAGAGAUUCAGAGGAGCUUAUUGGAAGGAGGUGGACAAGAUGGUCGACUAUAUGCAGCCAGGCGGAACACCUGCCACCGAGGGACUGGGACGACUGGCACCCUCCUAACAGAUUUUCAGCGGGGAGGCACUGAGAGUGGAUGGAGGGAAGACACAGAAGCUACGCUGAAGUGGGAGGAAGCUGCUGCACAGAGCUACCAUGCACUGGGACUAGCUCCUGGUCCCCAGUGACUCCAGGGGAACAGGUGAGUUAAACUGGCAAGGAACAACCUGCUCUCACCACAGGCCUCUGGAAUCCCGGCAGGAGGAGACUCCUUGACCACCACAGACACUUGAGCUGGCAGGGAGAGUUGCUUGGAGAAGUGGUAGGGGCAGCACUUCAGCCUGGGUGGAGCCCAGAGGGUUUGGUGUGGGAGCAUUUGCAAUAAAGCAUAGCCAGGGACAGCCAUCCCUCUAGGCUCGACUUGCUCCCAUGGCAGACUUUAACCCUAGGGGGACUGUUGAAACUAAAUUCUUCAGGGUGGUCUUGCCUGUCAGAUGAGGCCAGUUCAAUAACCUGAGCACCCCUUGGUUUUCUGGUCUCUCCUGGAGCCCCAGACUGGCCGUGCCUGCUUGCAGUGCAGCCUUGGGUAGCCCUGGGGGCCCGCAUCACAGCUCCUGUGCUGGCAAACCACACCAUGUUUGCCAGUGCAGUAGCUGUGAUGCGGGCCCCCAGGGCUACCCAAAGCAGAAAGCUCCAGCACAGCAGCCCCUAUGGACAUGCACCAGCCCAGCCACUUCCUUCCUCUACUGCAGUUUCCGCUGGGCCCAUGGCCAUCCCCCCCAAUCACUGCUGGUGCACAUGUGAGCAGGCAGAUCUUGCCUUCUCUGCCCUGCCAGUGUGCAUGUGUGCAUGUGCCCUGCCCUGCCACUGCUGCUGGCAUGAGUGAACUCAGCCUCCUCCUCCCCACACCAUGCCAUCAUUGCAGUCAAAGCCUUGGCAGGCACAGAGUCCACCAGCCUCACCUUCACCAGUGCCUUGCCCCUGCACUAACACUGCUGCUGGAGUGAAACUAGGCAGGGAGAACAGUGGACUUACCACACCCUGAGCAGCCACCCUUGCCUGCAAAAACUCAGACAGAGGGUGCACGCAGACCAGCACCUGCCAGUCUCCCGCUCCCAUGCUAACACCACUACCAGCGGGACAGCAUGCGAAGUUGCCAUUGGGCGUGAGGGGCCCACCUUCCCAUGUCAUGCUGCCUCCACUGCUGCUGCCAAUGCCCACAUGGAGGCUGGCACCUGGGCACCCCCUAGCACCCUGCCAUAGCCAAUGAGCAUGCACCCUGCUGCGCUGCCACUGCCACUACCACUGGCACAUGUGAAUGAGGACAGAUUCCACUGCCACUGCCCUACAAAAUGCUUUGGCUGGCACCACCCAUUGGAGUGUUGUGACCAGCAGUCAGGGAGCACCUUGGCUGCACCCAGCACAGUGGGUUCCUAACCUUGAGGAGCCAGAGAACGAAGUUGGGCCUGAUACCAAUCCCCUAGGGUUAGGGUAUGCAGUCUAGGAGUUGGAAGCCUAGCUUUGGCUCCCUGAAAUUUUCCAGAAAUGAAGCCAGUCAUUUGAACUCAUCUUAUAACACAAGCAAACCCUCAAGGUCAUCAAAUAGGAUACAAGAGAAAAAAAAACCAUCCCAAGGACAGCAACUUCAAAGACUGAAGGAACAUCAGUCUGCAAACAUGAGAAAGACCCAGAGCAAGAACUCUGAAAACACAAAAAACUAGAGUACCUUCUUUCUCCAAAUGACCACACUAGCUCUCCAGCCAGGGUUCUGAACCCGCACAUGUACCCCUAAACUUAAAAGAUUUUUAAAAAAGAGAUUCAGAGAAGGACUGUAGCUGUGGACCCAAGCUCCCUUCAAAGCACUGGCAGGUCAAUCGUUUGCAACGCAGACAGCUGUAUGUAGAGCUCUGUGAUCCACCCAAUUAUUGGCUCAUCAAGGAGUGUGCCACAUGCCAGAUGCUCUGCAGAACCCAACAGAGGGGUUGCUCCUCCAUGGAAACAACAAGAAGCUUUGAUCAAAGAGCCUGUAUUGACUCCUUCAGUGAAAUUCUUGACUGAAAUAAUCACCUUCUUAAAAUACACACAUGGUGAGGUUUGAAGAGGGGAAAUUGCCAUCCAGGUAAGAAACCUUGGCCUUGUCCCAAUUUAGUAGUGCUGAAGGUGUGUUCAUUUGAACAUAGAUCAUGUGCUAGGUACUGGGAGGAUACAGGAAUGAGCAUGGGAAUAAACUUUACAUAGCUCUUGUUCAAGCAGGAACUUUACAAUCUAGUUAGAAUAAAGAAUUAUCUGUGAGUCCUGGUUGGACAGUGUGUAUCCCAGCACUAUCUAGGGGUAAGGAUGCCUUCAUACCAACCUCGUCAUGACUGUGCUAAGUGGCAGGUCUGAUUUGGUUAUAGAACUGGAUACAUCAGACAGUUUUAACUUUAUGCUAUUAAAUAUUUGAACAUA